AUGUCAGCAGCUGCCAGUCUGGAGGCGUUCCCACAGCUGUGCAGAACUCAGCGCAGCGCGCUGCUGUUCGCGGCUGUUGCCGCUGCUGCUCCCCGGGCUGGGGCUGUUGCCCGCUACAAAUACGCCUCCAGUGUUCGCAGCUCUCAUCUUGCAGUACAGCGCCUGCAUGCACCCCAGCCUGAGGUCCAAGUGCAGGGACAGGAGCCACUGACUACCUCCAUGCUGGCCGCAGCACACCCCCAGGAACAGAAGCAGAUGCUGGGAGAACGCUUGUUCCCACUCAUCCAAACAAUGCAUUCAAACCUGGCUGGGAAGAUCACGGGAAUGCUGCUGGAGAUCCACAACUCUGAGCUGCUGCACAUGUUAGAGUUCCCCGAGUCUCUCCAUUCCAAGGUGGAUGAAGCUGUAGCAGUUCUACAGGCUCAUCAUGCCAAGAAAGAAGCUGCCCAGAAAGUGGGCGCUGUUGCUGCUGCUACCUCUUAGACAAGGAAAAACCGAUUCAAAAGCCAAAUAACCCCUCAUGGA